AGUCCCCACUGCUCAGCACUAGGCCGGCAGAAUCUGAGCGAUGUCUUCCACACUCCCUGCCCUGCUCUGCGUCGGGCUGUGUCUGAGUCAGAGGAUCAGCGCCCAGCAGCAGACUCUCCCAAAACCGUUCAUCUGGGCCGAGCCCCAUUUCAUGGUUCCAAAGGAAAAGCAAGUGACCAUCUGUUGCCAGGGAAAUUAUGGGGCUGUUGAAUACCAGCUGCACUUUGAAGGAAGCCUUUUUGCCGUGGACAGACCAAAACCCCCUGAGCGGAUUAACAAAGUCCAAUUCUACAUCCCGGACAUGAACUCCCGCAUGGCAGGGCAAUACAGCUGCAUCUAUCGGGUUGGGGAGCUCUGGUCAGAGCCCAGCAACUUGCUGGAUCUGGUGGUAACAGAAAUGUAUGACACACCCACCCUCUCGGUUCAUCCUGGACCCGAAGUGAUCUCGGGAGAGAAGGUGACCUUCUACUGCCGUCUAGACACUGCAACAAGCAUGUUCUUACUGCUCAAGGAGGGAAGAUCCAGCCACGUACAGCGCGGAUACGGGAAGGUCCAGGCGGAGUUCCCCCUGGGCCCUGUGACCACAGCCCACAGAGGGACAUACCGAUGUUUUGGCUCCUAUAACAACCAUGCCUGGUCUUUCCCCAGUGAGCCAGUGAAGCUCCUGGUCACAGGCGACAUUGAGAACACCAGCCUUGCACCUGAAGACCCCACCUUUCCUGGUGGUAACUGCCUUCUAAGCUCAGCGAG